AGUCGUUCUGAAGCGGCGGCCAGAGAAGAGUCAAGGGCACGAGCAUCGGGUAGCCAUGCCUUUCUUGGACAUCCAGAAAAGGUUCGGCCUUAACAUAGAUCGAUGGUUGACAAUCCAGAGUGGUGAACAGCCCUACAAGAUGGCUGGUCGAUGCCAUGCUUUUGAAAAAGAAUGGAUAGAAUGUGCACAUGGAAUCGGUUAUACUCGGGCAGAGAAAGAGUGCAAGAUAGAAUAUGAUGAUUUCGUAGAGUGUUUGCUUCGGCAGAAAACGAUGAGACGUGCAGGUACCAUCAGGAAGCAGCGGGAUAAGCUGAUAAAGGAAGGAAAGUACACCCCUCCACCUCACCACAUUGGCAAGGGGGAGCCUCGGCCCUGAACAGAGCAGCUGCUGAUGUCUGGAGGCUGAUUUUCCUGUUCUCUGUUCUCCACUGGAAAGGUUGUUUACGACAAACCUCCUUGUCAAAGUGUGUAAAAAUAAAGGAUUGCUCCAUCCUA